ACACCUCACGAAGACCCGCAGAUGCCACAAACUAACUGCUGGACUGCAGCGAAACCCGACCCCUGUUUGGAGGCACUCCAGGUUUCCGGAGGAUUGUCAUCUCCAUAGCUGCGGCAAGAAACUAAAUAAGACCCAUUUAUGCACAGUGAAGAUUCUGAGAGGAUUCUGCAGCAAAACAACAAUGGCCGCUCCACAGAGUCGCCCCAGACGCGGCGAGCUGAUCCUGCUGUGCGCGCUGCUGGGAACGCUGUGGGAAAUCGGGAGGGGACAGAUUCGCUACUCUGUGCCAGAAGAGACGGACAAAGGCUCCUUCGUGGGUAAUAUCUCCAAGGACCUGGGGCUGGACCCCCGGAAGCUGGCGAAGCACGGAGUCCGUAUCGUCUCCAGAGGUAGGACGCAGCUCUUUGCUCUGAACCCGCGCAGCGGCAGCUUGAUCACCGCGGGCAGGAUAGAUCGGGAGGAGCUCUGCGCUCAGAGCCCGCGGUGUCUGAUAAAUAUUAACACCCUGGUUGAGGAUAAAGGAAAACUCUUUGGGGUAGAAAUAGAAAUAAUUGAUAUUAACGAUAAUAACCCAAAAUUCCAGGUCGAAGAUCUAGAAGUAAAAAUUAACGAAAUCGCGGUUCCUGGAGCACGUUAUCCACUCCCAGAAGCUGUUGACCCGGAUGUGGGCGUGAACUCCCUCCAGAGCUACCAGCUCAGCCCCAAUCACCACUUCUCCCUGGACGUGCAGACUGGAGACAAUGGAGCCAUAAACCCAGAGCUGGUGCUGGAGCGCGCCCUGGACAGGGAGGAAGAGGCUGCUCACCACCUGGUCCUCACGGCCUCGGAUGGCGGCAAGCCGCCUCGCUCUAGCACAGUGCGCAUCCACGUGACAGUGUUGGAUACAAAUGACAAUGCCCCGGUUUUUCCUCACCCGAUUUACCGAGUGAAAGUCCUUGAGAACAUGCCCCCAGGCACGCGGCUGCUUACUGUAACAGCCAGCGACCCGGAUGAGGGAAUCAACGGAAAAGUGGCAUACAAAUUCCGGAAAAUUAAUGAAAAACAAACUCCGUUAUUCCAGCUUAAUGAAAAUACUGGGGAAAUAUCAAUAGCAAAAAGUCUAGAUUAUGAAGAAUGUUCAUUUUAUGAAAUGGAAAUACAAGCCGAAGAUGUGGGGGCACUUCUGGGGAGGACCAAAUUGCUCAUUUCGGUGGAAGAUGUAAAUGACAAUAGACCAGAAGUGAUCAUUACGUCUUUGUUUAGCCCAGUGUUAGAAAAUUCUCUUCCCGGGACAGUAAUUGCCUUCUUGAGUGUGCAUGACCAAGACUCUGGAAAGAAUGGUCAAGUUGUCUGUUACACACGUGAUAAUUUACCUUUUAAAUUAGAAAAGUCAAUAGGUAAUUAUUAUAGAUUAGUGACAAGGAAAUAUUUGGACCGAGAAAAUGUCUCUAUCUACAAUAUCACAGUGAUGGCCUCAGAUCUAGGAACACCACCUCUGUCCACUGAAACUCAAAUCGCUCUGCACGUGGCAGACAUUAACGACAACCCUCCUACUUUCCCUCAUGCCUCCUACUCAGCGUAUAUCCUAGAGAACAACCUGAGAGGAGCCUCCAUCUUUUCCUUGACUGCACACGACCCCGACAGCCAGGAGAAUGCCCAGGUCACUUACUCUGUGACCGAGGACACGCUGCAGGGGGCGCCCCUGUCCUCGUAUAUCUCCAUCAACUCUGACACCGGUGUCCUGUAUGCGCUGCAAUCUUUCGACUAUGAGCAGAUCCGAGACCUGCAGCUACUGGUAACAGCCAGCGACAGCGGGGACCCGCCCCUCAGCAGCAACAUGUCACUGAGCCUGUUCGUGCUGGACCAGAAUGACAACGCGCCCGAGAUCCUGUACCCCGCCCUCCCCACAGACGGUUCCACUGGCGUGGAGCUGGCGCCCCGCUCCGCAGAGCGUGGCUACCUGGUGACCAAGGUGGUGGCGGUGGACAGAGACUCGGGCCAGAACGCCUGGCUGUCCUACCGCCUGCUCAAGGCCAGCGAGCCGGGACUCUUCUCGGUGGGUCUGCACACGGGCGAGGUGCGCACGGCGCGAGCCCUGCUGGACAGAGAUGCGCUCAAGCAGAGCCUCGUGGUGGCCGUCCAGGACCAUGGCCAGCCCCCUCUCUCCGCCACUGUCACGCUCACCGUAGCCGUGGCUGACAGCAUCCCCGAAGUCCUGACCGAGUUGGGCAGUCUGAAGCCUUCGGUCGACCCGAACGAUUCGAGCCUUACACUCUAUCUCGUGGUGGCAGUGGCUGCCAUCUCCUGUGUCUUCCUCGCCUUUGUCGCUGUGCUUCUGGGGCUCAGGCUGAGGCGCUGGCACAAGUCACGCCUGCUCCAGGAUUCCGGUGGCAGAUUGGUAGGCGUGCCUGCCUCACAUUUUGUGGGUGUUGAGGAGGUACAGGCUUUCCUGCAGACCUAUUCCCAGGAAGUCUCCCUCACCGCCGACUCGCGGAAGAGUCACCUGAUCUUUCCCCAGCCCAACUACGCAGACAUGCUCAUCAGUCAGGAGGGCUGUGAGAAAAAUGAUUCUUUGUUAACAUCCGUAGAUUUUCAUGAAUAUAAGAAUGAAGCUGAUCAUGGUCAGCAAGCCCCGCCCAACACGGACUGGCGUUUCUCUCAGGCCCAGAGACCCGGCACCAGCGGCUCCCAAAAUGGCGAUGACACCGGCACCUGGCCCAACAACCAGUUUGACACAGAGAUGCUGCAAGCCAUGAUCUUGGCGUCCGCCAGUGAAGCUGCUGAUGGGAGCUCCACCCUGGGAGGGGGUGCCGGCACCAUGGGAUUGAGCGCCCGCUACGGACCCCAGUUCACCCUGCAGCACGUGCCCGACUACCGCCAGAAUGUCUACAUCCCAGGCAGCAAUGCCACACUGACCAACGCAGCUGGCAAGCGGGAUGGCAAGGCCCCAGCAGGUGGCAAUGGCAACAAGAAGAAGUCGGGCAAGAAGGAGAAGAAGUAACAUGGAGGCCAGGCCAAGAGCCACAGGGCGGCCUCUCCCCAACCAGCCCAGCUUCUCCUUACCUGCACCCAGGCCUCAGAGUUUCAGGGCUAACCCCCAGAAUACUGGUAGGGGCCAAGGCCAUGCUCCCCUUGGGAAACAGAAACAAGUGCCCAGUCAGCACCUACCCCUUCCCCCCCAGGGGGUUGAAUAUGCAAAAGCAGUUCCGCUGGGAACCCCCAUCCAAUCAACUGCUGUACCCAUGGGGGUAGUGGGGUUACUGUAGACACCAAGAACCAUUUGCCACACCCCGUUUAGUUACAGCUGAACUCCUCCAUCUUCCAAAUCAAUCAGGCCCAUCCAUCCCAUGCCUCCCUCCUCCCCACCCCACUCCAACAGUUCCUCUUUCCCGAGUAAGGUGGUUGGGGUGUUGAAGUACCAAGUAACCUACAAGCCUCCUAGUUCUGAAAAGUUGGAAGGGCAUCAUGACCUCUUGGCCUCUCCUUUGAUUCUCAAUCUUCCCCCAAAGCAUGGUUUGGUGCCAGCCCCUUCACCUCCUUCCAGAGCCCAAGAUCAAUGCUCAAGUUUUGGAGGACAUGAUCACCAUCCCCAUGGUACUGAUGCUUGCUGGAUUUAGGGAGGGCAUUUUGCUACCAAGCCUCUUCCCAACGCCCUGGGGACCAGUCUUCUGUUUUGUUUUUCAUUGUUUGACGUUUCCACUGCAUGCCUUGACUUCCCCCACCUCCUCCUCAAACAAGAGACUCCACUGCAUGUUCCAAGACAGUAUGGGGUGGUAAGAUAAGGAAGGGAAGUGUGUGGAUGUGGAUGGUGGGGGCAUGGACAAAGCUUGACACAUCAAGUUAUCAAGGCCUUGGAGGAGGCUCUGUAUGUCCUCAGGGGACUGACAACAUCCUCCAGAUUCCAGCCAUAAACCAAUAACUAGGCUGGACCCUUCCCACUACAUAAUAGGGCUCAGCCCAGGCAGCCAGCUUUGGGCUGAGCUAACAGGACCAAUGGAUUAAACUGGCAUUUCAGUCCAAGGAAGCUCGAAGCAGGUUUAGGACCAGGUCCCCUUGAGAGGUCAGAGGGGCCUCUGUGGGUGCUGGGUACUCCAGAGGUGCCACUGGUGGAAGGGUCAGCGGAGCCCCAGCAGGAAGGGUGGGCCAGCCAGGCCAUUCUUAGUCCCUGGGUUGGGGAGGCAGGGAGCUAGGGCAGGGACCAAAUGAACAGAAAGUCUCAGCCCAGGAUGGGGCUUCUUCAACAGGGCCCCUGCCCUCCUGAAGCCUCAGUCCUUCACCUUGCCAGGUGCCGUUUCUCUUCCGUGAAGGCCACUGCCCAGGUCCCCAGUGCGCCCCCUAGUGGCCAUAGCCUGGUUAAAGUUCCCCAGUGCCUCCUUGUGCAUAGACCUUCUUCUCCCACCCCCUUCUGCCCCUGGGUCCCCGGCCAUCCAGCGGGGCUGCCAGAGAACCCCAGACCUGCCCUUACAGUAGUGUAGCGCCCCCUCCCUCUUUCGGCUGGUGUAGAAUAGCCAGUAGUGUAGUGCGGUGUGCUUUUACGUGAUGGCGGGUGGGCAGCGGGCGGCGGGCUCCGCGCAGCCGUCUGUCCUUGAUCUGCCCGCGGCGGCCCGUGUUGUGUUUUGUGCUGUGUCCACGCGCUAAGGCGACCCCCUCCCCCGUACUGACUUCUCCUAUAAGCGCUUCUCUUCGCAUAGUCACGUAGCUCCCACCCCACCCUCUUCCUGUGUCUCACGCAAGUUUUAUACUCUAAUAUUUAUAUGGCUUUUUUUCUUCGACAAAAAAAUAAUAAAACGUUUCUUCUGAAAA